AGACCACGCCCACCAAGGGCUGGCCGCAGCCACUGUAGCUGAGCUCAGAGCCUUCUGUGUGGUUUGCGGGGGCAAGGUCAGCUGCCCCCUGCCCUCUCUCUGGGGCUAUUUGAGGAAUGCGGCCUUUUUGCAUAAGAAAGGCUUUUCUCUACAGUAACUGUGGUCGCUGAUCAAUGACACCUUCCUGAUACUUUGACGAAGGUAAUUGGGACUCCCAUCAAGUCUCCACACAGCUAGCAGCCACGUGGGGCACUUCUCCAGAUGUAGUCUUGCUCUGUUGCCCGGGCUAGAAUGCAGUGGCACAAUCUCGGCUCACCACAACCUCCGCCUCCCAGGUUCAAGUGAUUCUCCUGCCUCAGCCUCCCAAAUAGCUGGGAUUACAGGUGUCCGCCACCAUGUCCAACUAAUUUUUGUAUUUUUAGUAGAGACAGGUUUCACUGUCUUGGCCAGGCUGGUCUCGAACUCCAGACCUCGUGAUCCACCCACCUCGGGUUCCCAAAGUGCUGAGAUUACAGGCGUGACCCACCACGCCUGGCCAGGAAUGACUGUCAACUAUAUUUUCUUAACAUAUGUAUUCCUACACAACAUCAGUUUUGUAAUAGUUUAUUUUUGUUUUGUUUUGCAAUUUUUUUCUUUUAUUGUAAGGAAAGAAGUACAUUUUUUCAGCGUGUAAGAAUGCAAAAGUAAUUAUCAGAUGUUUGUCACAUCUUAACAAAAUAGGACCUUAUUUUCCUAGAUGUUGCUGCAUUCAGUCCCUUUCUUGGUAUGGUAAAAGCAUCAAUCAGCCAGGGAGGCAACUAUAAAUACAGAAGAGCAGUUUCCUACAGAUAGUCAACCAUGCUACCCCUCUUACUGACUUAAUUUUAAUAUUGGAGCCUGGCACAAUUAACCUAGUUUCCUCGUAAACACAAGAACAACGUACUGCAAUCAAUGUAGGCAUAUACAGGCUCUUAAAGUUCUGAGAAGCAGCAACAUAUGUAAGUGGAACUCAGAAGGCAACAUUCCCUGAACAUACUCUUCCACCAGAAUCUCCUCUACAGAUUUUUGCUGCCCCUUUUACCAGUGGCUGAAUCUACUUUCUCUUAUGUUUUGCUCCAUCACCCAGGCGGAGUGCAGUGGUGCCAUCACAGCUUACUGCAGUCUCCACCUCUCAGGCUCAAGUGAUUCUCCUACCUCAGCCUCCCGAGUAGCUGGGACCAGAGGGAUCGCUUACACCUGAGACGAACUACAGAACAGCACGUACCAGAGGUGGAAGUCCAAGUCAAACGCAGAAGGACUGCCUCACUGAGCAACCAAGAGUGUCAGUUGUACCCGAGGCGUUCUCAGCAGCAGCAAGUACCUGUGGUGGAUUUCCAGGCUGAACUGAGGCAGGCAUUCUUAGCUGAGACACCAAGAGGUGGUUAAAGCCAUAUUGGAGUAGCGAGGAAUCUGAUUCCAAGCAAAAACCAGGCUCCAUCUACUCUUUGAAGCUUCUGCCCAGCUUGCAUUGUUUCUAGGAGAACCUGCGUCAUACCUUUAUCUAUAGCCUUCCCCUAGGUCUUCAGAAGCAUCAAGUUUUAACUGUGGACAUUGGAUUUGGUGGAACAGCAAUCAUGACUGUUGGCAAGAGUAGCAAGAUGCUGCAGCACAUUGACUAUAGAAUGAGAUGUAUCCUGCAAGAUGGCCGAAUCUUCAUUGGCACCUUUAAGGCUUUUGACAAGCAUAUGAAUUUGAUCCUCUGUGAUUGUGAUGAGUUCAGAAAGAUCAAGCCAAAGAAUGCGAAGCAACCAGAGCGUGAAGAAAAGCGGGUUUUGGGUCUGGUGUUGCUGCGUGGGGAGAACUUGGUAUCCAUGACUGUGGAGGGGCCACCCCCCAAAGAUACUGGCAUUGCUCGGGUACCACUUGCUGGAGCUGCUGGAGGCCCUGGGGUUGGUAGGGCAGCUGGUAGAGGAGUACCAGCUGGUGUGCCAAUUCCCCAGGCCCCUGCUGGAUUGGCAGGCCCUGUCCGAGGAGUUGGGGGACCAUCCCAGCAGGUAAUGACUCCACAGGGAAGAGGCACUGUAGCAGCUGCUGCUGUUGCUGCGACUGCCAGUAUUGCUGGAGCCCCAACACAGUACCCACCAGGACGGGGCACUCCGCCCCCACCCGUCGGCAGAGCAACCCCACCUCCAGGCAUUAUGGCUCCUCCACCUGGUAUGAGACCACCCAUGGGCCCACCAAUUGGGCUUCCCCCUGCUCGAGGGACGCCAAUAGGCAUGCCGCCUCCGGGAAUGAGACCCCCUCCACCAGGCAUUAGAGGUCCACCUCCCCCAGGAAUGCGUCCACCAAGACCUUAGCAUACUGUUGAUCCAUCUCAGUCACUUUUUCCCCUGCAAUGCGUCUUGUGAAAUUGUGUAGAGUGUUUGUGAGCUUUUUGUUCCCUCAUUCUGCAUUAAUAAUAGCUAAUAAUAAAUGCAUAGAGCAAUUAAACUGUGAGGUACUGUUGUAUAUAUUUUUUUGCCUGUUGAUUUUGAUGAGAUCUUAAGUUACUGUGGAUGAGGGUGAUGCCUAUUAAGCAGUUGAUUCAAAUCAUAUUCUCUUUAAUUCUUAGGAUAAAAAGGUUUUCUGCUAUCUAA